GUGAGUCGCAGCAGGAGCCGCAGCCGGAGUCACAGCCGCAGCCAGAGCCGCAGCCAAAGCCUCAGAGAGCAGGAGUUGGAGCGCAGGCCCUGCUGGAUCCGCGCCUAGCUCGCCGCCAGGCACCGGCCGGAGGACGGGCCGUGGUGUCAGCUCACUGCCCGGGCGCUGUGGGAGGCAGCGAGCCCGCGACCCCCCGGGCCGGGCACCGCCAGGCGCGGAGCCCAGAUCGCCCCCCUGCCAGGCCUGGUCACGGCCAGAGCACGCAGGAGUUCCCAGGGUCUGGAUCUGCGCGCACCCUAAUGACCUGGGGACUGAAGAGAAAAAAGGAACGAGGAUUUCAUCUAAAAGCAUAACGUGGGCACUAGGCGAGGAGGAAAGUGGAGACCACCUGGCACGGGGCAGAGGUGCCUGGAGCCCACGCUUGAGCAUCGGAGACCCUGGCAUCCUAGCAGCCGCGACCUUGGCUCUGCCCUGUCUGAGCUGGAAACACAGCUUAGCUUCUAGACAUCGCUGGCACAGGCCUGGCACAAGUAAGCAGUGUCCUCACCUGUCUGAAACGGGACACGGGGUCGGAGGAACCAGGAUCUAGCCUGGCCCCAAGCGGAACUCUCUGGUGGCCCAGAGGUCGUCACUGGGGAGCCCGCCUCCUGCCCUAGCCUCACUGGUGCGGAUGUGCCGCUGCCCGCCGGAGCACCAUGAUGGCAGGAUGACCUCAGCCGAAGUAGGAGCAGCAGCUGGUGGUGCUCAGGCGGCUGGGCCCCCCGAGUGGCCCCCUGGCAGCCCUCAGGCCCUCCGGCAGCCUGGCCGGGCCCGAGUGGCCAUGGCAGCACUGGUGUGGCUGCUGGCGGGAGCCAGCAUGUCAAGCCUCAACAAGUGGAUCUUCACAGUGCACGGCUUUGGGCGGCCCCUGCUGCUGUCGGCCCUGCACAUGCUGGUGGCAGCCCUGGCAUGCCACCGGGGGGCACGGCGCCCCAUGCCAGGCGGCACUCGCUGCCGAGUCCUACUGCUCAGUCUCACCUUUGGCACGUCCAUGGCCUGCGGCAACGUGGGCCUAAGGGCUGUGCCCCUGGACCUGGCACAACUGGUUACUACCACCACACCUCUGUUCACCCUGGCCCUGUCGGCGCUGCUGCUGGGCCGCCGCCACCACCCACUUCAGUUGGCCGCCAUGGGUCCGCUCUGCCUGGGGGCCGCCUGCAGCCUGGCUGGAGAGUUCCGGACACCCCCUACCGGCUGUGGCUUCCUGCUCGCAGCCACCUGCCUCCGCGGACUCAAGUCGGUUCAGCAAAAUCCUGAUCUGGUCCAUUCAGCAGAGGACUGCAGAAGUCUGAGGAGCCUUAAGAUAUCAACUUAAAGCAAUGGGCUCGUCGCAGAAAGGAAUAGCCUGUGCCGGGUCUUCAGAGAAAUCCUGGCCUCGGCUCCACGCCCCUGAGCAGCCCCACCCUGGCUCAACCUGUUACCCGCCCUGCCGGCAAGCCGGGGUCACUGCAGUCCCCGUGGCGAAGCAGGGUCAGCUCAGCUCACCGCACCCCACUCCAUCCAGCCCUGCCCAUCUCUACGGCAACGGGCCGGGUCGCACCAGGGCUGCAGCCGAGAGACAGUCUCACCGCUUCCGUAGCCGCCCGGGCUCUGUGCGCAUGUGCGACACUCCCUCCCCGGCCCCGCCCCCUUAUGCGUCUCCCAGGCAACGCGCCGCGCGGGGCUCCAGGUUCCGCCCAGGGACUAACUCCAGGUCUGCGCGCGUCCAACGAGCACGGCUCUCAACCGGCCUCCUGGCGCCCAACGACCAUGGCUUCCAACCGGCCUCCGUGCGCCCAACGACCAUGACUCCCAACCGGCCUCCAGUUUCCAACUGUUUCUCGAACAGGGAAGCCGCCAUGACACAGCUGACUACGCCCUUGGUCACAGGGGACCUGAGAUCCUCCACGAUUUACGGGACCGGCGCCACCUCGGGCUCGAACCACCCUCUCGAUAGGGCCGCCGCUAAGUAAUCGGCGUAGGGGUUCAGCCGCACAUCUCCUUCCCGCGCCGCGGACCGAGCAGUCGUUGGUGCUCUUCAGGUGCGGCCUGGGUGCCCAGAGCCUUCGUUAGACUCUCGGACCCGCAAGGGAGCCCGAACUCUUUCAGACUCGCUCUCCCUCAGCCGGACCUCGGCCCUUUUUCACACCCCAGGGGAGUCUGGAUUUCUCAUAGUCCUGGGCACCAGCCCCUUCCCAGUCUAGCUCUUGGGACUCCCUGAAGCCGGAACUCCCUCGCCUGGACUCCCGGGAGAACCUGGAAUCCCCAUCUCCAGUCCACAUUUUCUCAGAAUCUGUCCUAGCCCUUCAGUCUCCCAGGCAUGACAUCGUGUGGUCCCAGCGCCCUAGGUGGUGAGCUGUGACUCUCCUUAGAGCCUGGCGAGGCCGAGGUCCUCCCCAGCUCGAACCCAUCCCACACUCCCCUUCUCAGCCUCUGUGUUCCCCAGUGGUCCUGGAAAAGCCCCCAGUUCCCUCUGCCUGGCCCCAAUCCUCACAAACCCAAUUACCCACGCUCCUUUCCAUUCCAUAACCCCCAUCACUGCAUCCUCCAGGCUCCCAUCCAUGGAGGACUUGAGGUGGAAAGCAAUUUGGUUCAAAAUAACCAUUAUUUAUUACUUGAAAGGGAAUAUUUCCAGUCGUUGCCAGCCUCCUCCCCUUCUAGUAUUGGUAAAUUUUUUGCACCACUGAGUGGGUGAAGAGUUUUAUGCGUCUUUAAAUGUUUUAAGGAUUUUUUUAAAAAAACAAAAAACUCUCAGGA